AGCUUGGCCGGGCGCGGAGCGGGGCGCAUGGCGCCGGGCGCACUGCGCGGGGGCUGCGAACAAAGGGCCCCCGGCGGCGGCGCGAGGACGGCCGCGCUCGGACCCUGGCCCUGGCCCAGCCCUGGCCCGGCCCCCUCCCCAGGCGCGGCGCCCCCCAGGAGCCGAAAAAUGAGCGGCGCCCUGCUCUGGCCGUUGCUCCCGCUCCUGCUCCUGCUGCUGUCGGCGCGGGACGGCGUGCGCGCCGCGCAGCCUCAGGCCCCGGGUUACUUGAUUGCAGCUCCCUCUGUUUUUCGCGCGGGCGUGGAGGAAGUCAUCAGCGUGACCAUCUUUAACUCUCCAAGGGAAGUCACGGUCCAGGCUCAGCUGGUGGCCCAGGGUGAGCCGGUGGUGCAGAGCCAGGGAGCCAUCCUGGAUAAAGGGACAAUCAAACUCAAGGUGCCCACGGGCCUCCGGGGCCAAGCGCUUCUGAAAGUGUGGGGCCGCGGCUGGCAGGCGGAGGAGGGGCCCCUCUUUCACAACCAGACCUCGGUGACCGUGGACGGCCGGGGCGCUUCUGUAUUCAUCCAGACGGACAAGCCUGUGUACAGACCCCAGCACCGAGUGCUCAUAAGCAUCUUCACCGUCUCUCCAAAUCUGAGGCCUGUCAACGAGAAGCUGGAAGCCUACAUCCUGGACCCCCGAGGCUCUCGGAUGAUAGAGUGGAGACACUUAAAGCCGUUCUGCUGCGGCAUCACCAACAUGAGCUUCCCCUUGUCCGACCAGCCUGUGUUGGGAGAAUGGUUCAUUUUUGUUGAAAUGCAAGGCCACGCGUACAACAAGUCUUUUGAAGUUCAGAAGUAUGUGUUGCCCAAGUUUGAGCUUCUGAUUGACCCGCCCCGGUAUAUCCAAGACCUGGACGCCUGUGAGACAGGCACUGUGCGGGCCAGGUAUACCUUUGGGAAACCUGUGGCUGGUGCCUUAAUGAUCAACAUGACUGUUAAUGGUGUAGGGUACUACAGCCACGAGGUGGGACGCCCUGUCCUCAGAACAACCAAGAUCCUCGGCUCCCGGGACUUCGACAUCUGCGUGAGGGACAUGAUCCCAGCGGACGUCCCUGAGCACUUCCGGGGCAGGGUCAGCAUCUGGGCCAUGGUGACCAGUGUGGACGGGAGCCAGCAGGUCGCGUUCGAUGACUCCACCCCCGUGCAGAGGCAGCUGGUGGACAUCCGGUACUCCAAGGACACGAGGAAGCAGUUCAAGCCGGGCCUGGCCUACGUGGGGAAGGUGGAGCUAUCCUACCCCGAUGGCAGCCCAGCUGAGGGGGUGACGGUCCAGAUUAAGGCAGAGCUGACACCAAAGGAUAACAUCUACACCAGUGAAGUUGUGUCCCAGCGUGGACUAGUGGGGUUUGAAAUCCCCUCCAUCCCCACGUCAGCCCAGCACGUGUGGCUGGAGACCAAGGUGAUGGCACUGAACGGGAAGCCUGUGGGGGCUCAGUACCUGCCCAGCUACCUCUCCCUCGGCAGCUGGUACUCCCCCAGCCAGUGCUACCUGCAGCUGCAGCCACCCUCCCACCCACUGCAGGUUGGGGAAGAAGCCUAUUUUUCUGUGAAGUCCACAUGUCCCUGCAACUUUACCCUGUACUACGAGGUGGCUGCACGGGGCAAUAUUGUGCUAUCGGGCCAGCAGCCUGCCCACACCACCCAGCAGCGAAGCAAGCGGGCGGCCCCUGCCCUGGAGAAACCGAUUCGUUUAACACACCUUUCUGAGACAGAGCCCCCACCAGCCCCAGAAGCUGAGGUCGACGUGUGUGUGACCUCUCUUCAUCUGGCCGUGACCCCCAGCAUGGUCCCCCUUGGUCGCCUGCUGGUCUUCUACGUCAGGGAGAAUGGAGAAGGGGUCGCCGACAGCCUUCAGUUUGCAGUCGAGACCUUCUUCGAAAACCAGGUUUCAGUGACGUAUUCAGCAAAUGAGACCCAACCUGGGGAGGUUGUCGACCUGCGGAUCAGGGCUGCAAGGGGCAGCUGUGUGUGCGUCGCCGCAGUUGAUAAGAGUGUCUACCUGCUCAGGUCUGGGUUCCGGCUGACUCCUGCCCAGGUUUUCCAGGAACUGGAAGAUUAUGAUGUUUCUGAUUCCUUUGGCGUGUCCAGGGAGGAUGGUCCUUUUUGGUGGGCUGGGCUGACGGCACAACGACGCCGGCGCUCCUCUGUCUUCCCGUGGCCUUGGGGCAUCACCAAGGACUCUGGGUUUGCCUUCACCGAAACGGGACUGGUGGUGAUGACCGACCGAGUGAGCCUGAACCACCGGCAGGACGGUGGCCUCUACACCGAUGAGGCUGUCCCCGCUUUCCAGCCCCACACAGGGAGCCUGGUGGCAGUGGCUCCUUCCAGGCACCCCCCCAGAACAGAGAAGAGAAAAAGGACUUUCUUCCCCGAAACAUGGAUUUGGCAUUGUCUCAACAUCAGUGACCCAUCUGGUGAGGGGACACUCAGUGUGAAGGUCCCGGACUCCAUCACCAGCUGGGUGGGUGAGGCCGUGGCCCUGUCCACCUCUCAGGGCUUAGGCAUCGCCGAGCCCUCCCUGCUGAAGACCUUCAAGCCCUUCUUCGUGGACUUCAUGCUCCCCGCUCUCAUCAUCCGUGGGGAGCAGGUCAAGAUCCCGCUCAGUGUCUACAACUACAUGGGCACCUGCGCUGAGGUGUACAUGAAGCUCUCGGUUCCCAAGGGCAUCCAGUUUGUUGGGCAUCCUGGCAAACGCCAUGUGACCAAGAAGAUGUGUGUGGCCCCCGGGGAGGCUGAGCCCAUCUGGGUCGUUCUGUCCUUCAGCGACCUGGGACUCAACAACAUCACGGCCAAAGCCCUUGCUUACGGAGACACAAAUUGCUGCCGGGAUGGGAGGUCCAGCAAACACCCUGAGGAGAAUCACGCCGACAGGAGGGUCCCCAUCGGGGUGGAUCACGUCAGGCGCAGUGUGAUGGUUGAGGCGGAAGGAGUCCCCCGGGCGUACACCUACAGCGCAUUCUUCUGUCCCAGUGAGAGAGUCCACAUCUCCACCCCCAACAAGUAUGAGUUCCAGUAUGUGCAGCGGCCACUGCGCCUCACCCGCUUUGAUGUGGCUGUGCGAGCUCACAAUGAUGCCCGUGUGGCCUUGUCUUCUGGGCCCCAGGACACAGCAGGCAUGAUCGAGAUCGUCCUGGGGGGGCAUCAGAACACCAGGUCAUGGAUCUCCACCAGCAAGAUGGGAGAGCCCGUGGCCAGUGCACACACGGCCAAGAUCCUCUCCUGGGAUGAAUUCAGAACAUUCUGGAUCAGCUGGCGUGGUGGCCUUAUCCAGGUUGGCCAUGGUCCAGAGCCAUCCAAUGAGUCUGUCAUUGUGGCCUGGACCCUCCCGAGGCCACCAGAGGUCCAGUUCAUUGGCUUUUCCACCGGCUGGGGCUCCAUGGGUGAAUUCCGAAUCUGGAGGAAGAUGGAGGUGGACGAGAGCUACAGCGAGGCCUUCACCCUGGGGGUCCCACACGGCGCCAUCCCUGGGUCUGAGCGAGCCACCGCCUCCAUCAUCGGGGACGUCAUGGGGCCAACCCUGAACCACCUCAACAACCUCCUGCGGCUGCCGUUUGGCUGUGGAGAGCAGAACAUGAUCCACUUUGCACCCAACGUCUUUGUCUUGAAGUAUCUUCAGAAAACCCAGCAGCUCAGCCCUGAGGUGGAGAGAGAGACCACCGACUACCUAGUACAAGGCUACCAGCGCCAGCUGACCUACAAGCGCCAGGAUGGCUCCUACAGCGCGUUUGGGGAGCGGGACGCAUCGGGGAGCAUGUGGCUCACAGCCUUUGUCCUGAAGUCCUUCGCACAGGCUCGCAGCUUUAUCUUCGUGGACCCCCGGGAGCUGGCUGCCGCCAAGAGCUGGAUCAUCCAGCAGCAGCAGGCCGAUGGCUCCUUCCUGGCCGUGGGCAGGGUCCUGAACAAGGACAUCCAGGGUGGGAUCCACGGCACUGUCCCGCUGACAGCCUACGUGGUGGUUGCUCUCCUGGAAACAGGCACAGCCUCAGAGGAGGAGAGAGGCUCCACUGACAAAGCGAGGCACUUCCUGGAGUCUGCUGCGCCCCUGGCCAUGGACCCUUAUAGCUGUGCCCUGACUACCUACGCGCUGACCCUGCUCCGCAGCCCGGCAGCCCCUGAGGCACUGCGCAAGCUCCGUAGCCUGGCCAUCAUGCGAGAUGGGGUCACCCACUGGAGCCUGUCAAAUUCCUGGGACGUGGACAAGGGCACAUUCUUGAGCUUCAGUGACAGGGUCUCUCAGUCAGUGGUCUCGGCCGAGGUGGAAAUGACAGCCUACGCCCUUCUGACCUACACUCUGCUGGGUGACGUGGCUGCCGCCCUGCCUGUGGUGAAGUGGCUGUCCCAGCAGCGAAAUGCACUUGGGGGCUUCUCCUCCACUCAGGACACCUGCGUGGCUCUGCAGGCCUUGGCUGAAUAUGCCAUCUUGUCCUAUGCUGGAGGCAUCAACCUCACUGUCUCCCUGGCCUCCACCAACCUGGACUACCAGGAAACCUUCGAGCUGCACAGGACCAACCAGAAGGUUCUGCAGACAGCAGCGAUCCCCAGCCUCCCCACGGGGCUGUUUGUGAGUGCCAAGGGGGACGGCUGCUGCCUGAUGCAGAUUGAUGUCACCUACAAUGUGCCUGACCCGGUGGCCAAGCCAGCUUUCCAGCUGCUCGUAAGCCUCCAGGAGCCUGAGGCCCAGGGACGCCCGCCCCCCAUGCCUGCCUCCGCAGCUGAGGGUUCCCGAGGAGACUGGCCCCCAGCUGACGAUGAUGACCCAGCGGCCGAUCAGCAUCACCAGGAAUACAAGGUGAUGCUGGAGGUGUGCACCAGGUGGCUGCAUGCAGGGUCUUCCAAUAUGGCUGUCCUGGAGGUGCCCCUGCUGUCAGGCUUCCGGGCAGACAUCGAGAGCCUGGAGCAGCUGCUCCUUGACAAGCACAUGGGGAUGAAGAGGUAUGAAGUGGCUGGACGCCGAGUGCUCUUCUACUUUGAUGAGAUCCCCAGCCGGUGCCUGACGUGCGUGCGGUUCCGUGCUCUCCGGGAGUGCGUGGUGGGCAGGACGUCGGCGCUGCCAGUCUCCGUGUACGACUACUACGAACCCGCCUUCGAGGCCACUCGCUUCUACAACGUCAGCACCCACAGCCCACUCGCCCGGGAACUGUGCGCCGGACCCGCGUGCAACGAAGUGGAGCGCGCCCCUGCCCGGGGCCCGGGCUGGUUCCCCGGCGAGUCGGGCCCUGCCGUGGCCCCUGAGGAGGGGGCGGCGAUCGCGCGAUGCGGCUGCGACCACGACUGCGGCGCCCAGGGGAACCCGGUGUGCGGCUCCGACGGGGUGGUCUACGCCAGCGCCUGCCGCCUGCGGGAGGCCGCCUGCCGCCAGGCCGCGCCCCUGGAGCCCGCGCCUCCCAGCUGCUGCGCCCUCGAGCAGCGGCUGCCGGCCUCGUCGUCCUCCACCUACGGGGAUGACCUGGCUUCUGUGGCCCCGGGGCCUUUACAGCAGGACGUGAAGCUGAAUGGAGCCGGCCUUGAGGUGGAGGACUCAGACCCUGAGCCUGAAGGGGAGGCGGAGGACAGAUUUGUGUAAUCUCAACCAUAGUCAACAAACAGCCCAUCUGCACAGGAUCCUUCCAGCUGCUCUUCCAUAACUUCAUCUCUCCCCUCAACACCUGCAACCACUAAGCCAUUUUCCCCCUACCCGUCUGUAAUUUUGUUAUUUUGAGAAUGCCAGGUAAAUGGAAUCAGAGCGGAUAAUCUUUGGAGCAUGAUUCCCUUGCAUUCACCUGUGUUGUUUCGUGUAUCCAUAGUUUAUUCUUUUUUUAAUCUGGGCUCACUGCAAUCUCCGCCUCCUGGGUUCAAGCGAUUCUCCUGUCUCAGCCUCCCCAGAAGCUGGGAUUACAGGGGCCCGCCACCAUGCCCGGCUAAUUUUUUUUGUAUUUUUAGUAGAGGUGGGGUUUCACCAUGUUGGCCAGGCUGGUCUUGAACUCUUGACCUCAGGUGAUCCACCCGCGUUGGCCUCCCAAAGCGCUGGUAUUGCAGGCAUGAGCCACCAUGCCAGGCCUAUUCUUUUAUUUUUCAAACGAGGUCUCACUGUGUUGCCCAGGCUGGAGUGUAGUGGCGUGGUCAUGGCUCACUGCAGCCUUGACCUCCUGAGCUCAAGUGAUCCUCUUGCCUCAGCCUCCUGAGUAGCUGGGACCACAGGCACACACUACCACCACGCCCAGCUAGUGUGUGUGUGUGUGUGUGUGUGUGUGUGUGUGUGUGUGUUGUAGAGAUGGGGUCUCUGUAUGUUGCCCAAGCUGGAGUGCCAUGGCUGUUCAUAGACAUGAUCAUUGUGCACUGCAGCCUCAAAUUCCUGGGCUCAAGUGAUCCUCCCAUCUCAGUCUCCCAAAGCUUUGGGAUUACAGGCGUGAGCCACUGUGCCCGGCCUGGAGUUUGUUCUUUUGUAUUGCUGGGUAGUGUGCUAUGGGUAGCUUUUCGAUUUGGUUGGUGGUCUGACACAAGCUACUCCCCUCUUACCGCACAUGGACACCCAGAGCCCAUCACUGUGGUCCACUGGAAGGGGAAAGGAGGCAGAGUUGUACAGUGCCAGGCCUGGGCCAUGUGUCCCCCAUCCAGUUGGGGUUCUGCCAUCUAAAUGAGGAGGUGGCAGCUGGCCUGAGCCCCGUGGAGUUGGGUUCAGGAAAGGGGUGUGGGGUCCCAUCCCGAAGUCCUGGCGGCCCCAUAGGAAUCUUUCUCCUCUCCUGGCCAGUCAGAGCGGCUUCUCUUCCUAACGGCUGCCCUGCUGAGAGCAGGACGACACCAUCUGGCUGCAUCCUGUCCCUAUCAGCCUGUGACUCUGUAUGGUGGGUGGGCAGACCUCAGCCCAGGUGACACCUGCCUCUAAAUGAACCCAAGGAACAGAAUGACAGAGAUCUGCCCGUCCCUAGGAUGAGACUCUUGGGACCCAGGUGUGGGCUCAGCAGUCACCGGUGUGGUGCAGGGGGGACAGCUGGAGGUCCCUUGGGAGAUCCCCCACCUUCCUAGCUACAGCUGGAGCUCCAAGCACCCCAACCCCCCAGCCUUGGAGCUGGGCAUCAUUUUCCUGGGGCCACGGCAGCUCCCACAGCCUGACAUUCUGUUCCCGGGAGAAGAAACAUUCCCAGAAAGCACUCGUGUGGCCAAAAGCCUCUUUCUGAGCAAACACGAUGUGGACUAAAUUAGCAAAACAUCCAGCCGGUGGGCAACUUCAAAACGGAACAGGCUGCGUUUCUCUGAAACACAAAGCCCCGGCCUCCCUUUGGGGCACCCAGGACCCCAAAUUGCCCUAAGACUGUCCCAGCUCUCGCACCCUCUGCCUUCGCCCCCCGGGGACCUCGGGCUCACAUCACAAGGCCCUGCGGGGAAGCAGAUGGCUCUCAGCAAAUGCACUUUCAGCUUCCGGCUGCCGGGGCUGGGUGACCCCGGUGCUUCCUCACCGUGAGUUCCUGAUGUCCUCGUGCCCAGAGGACCAGCCCACUCCCAGGGCCCCCAGGCCCAGAACCUGCCUGCCUUGGGGGGCCCUACCAGCUGCCUGCCACCAGUACCAGCAGACUUUGAUUCCCCUUUGUGACCCCUGGCACCUGCUUAUGUCUGCAUUUGCCCAUCUUCUCCGGGGUGGUAUUUAUUUCAGCCAACACCGCUCAGCCCUGAUCUCUGCCAGCACGGAGGCCCCUCGCUGCCUGUGAGAUCAAGGUCUGAGGCUGCCCUGGCCGGUGGGUUCCCCACCCCUGGCACCCUACAAGCGACAGGCCCUGUGGCUCCUUCCUCAGCCCGAGGCCCCGUGCCCACUUGCUGUAGAGGAUGUUGUAAGAUAAAACCUCAUCUCCAGGGUCACAGCCGGGCCUCGGCCUCCUGUGAGCAGCGGGAACCUGGAAAGCAGCACCCAGAGCGCCAGCCCGUUCCACAGAUGGGGCCAGACUCCGGCCCCUCAGAGACAUAGUGGCCGGGUGGUGGGGGCCCACAGGCCAGGGCUUCUGAGCCCUGUCUUCGUCUACAGCCCAGCCUUUCAGAGUGGUGGGGAGGAGGGUUUAUGGAUGUCAAACACCUGCACCUUGAGAUAAUCCUACAACCACAUGCAGUUGUGGGACCGCAGUUUGGUCCUGGGGACCAUUCAUACCCACACACCCAGCUUGUGCCUGUGGUUAACAUCUCAGAAAACUCUGGUAAAUGAUCACUCCAGGAUAUUGACAAGAAUACACGUUACUGAUCUUACUCACA